ACUCGCCACCUCCUCUUCCACCCCUGCCAGGCCCAGCAGCCACCACAGCGCCUGCUUCCUCGGCCCUGAAAUCAUGCCCCUAGGUCUCCUGUGGCUGGGCCUAGCCCUGUUGGGGGCUCUGCAUGCCCAGGCCCAGGACUCCACCUCAGACCUGAUCCCAGCCCCACCUCUGAGCAAGGUCCCUCUGCAGCAGAACUUCCAGGACAACCAAUUCCAGGGGAAGUGGUAUGUGGUAGGCCUGGCAGGGAAUGCAAUUCUCAGAGAAGACAAAGACCCGCAAAAGAUGUAUGCCACCAUCUAUGAGCUGAAAGAAGACAAGAGCUACAAUGUCACCUCCGUCCUGUUUAGGAAAAAGAAGUGUGACUACUGGAUCAGGACUUUUGUUCCAGGUUGCCAGCCCGGCGAGUUCACGCUGGGCAACAUUAAGAGUUACCCUGGAUUAACGAGUUACCUCGUCCGAGUGGUGAGCACCAACUACAACCAGCAUGCUAUGGUGUUCUUCAAGAAAGUUUCUCAAAACAGGGAGUACUUCAAGAUCACCCUCUACGGGAGAACCAAGGAGCUGACUUCGGAACUAAAGGAGAACUUCAUCCGCUUCUCCAAAUCUCUGGGCCUCCCUGAAAACCACAUCGUCUUCCCUGUCCCAAUCGACCAGUGUAUCGACGGCUGAGUGCACAGUGAGUGUGGCUGGGCGGCUGCGAGGGGGCUUGUGGGAGGCCAGGGUGCAGUGGGCUGGGGGUCUUGGGCCUGCCUUUGCUCAUCCCCCUGCCCCCCAGCACUGCUGCUGUCUUUAUUCUGCUGUCCCCAUCUCGGGUGCCUCCCAUUUCCCCACCCAUCACCCUCAUAUCCACCUCUGUCCAGGGUGCCGCCAGCUGCCGCACCAGCCCGAACACCAUUGAGGGAGCUGGGAGACCCUCCCCACAGUGCCACCCAUGCAGCUGCUCCCCAGGCCACCCCGCUGAUGGAGCCCCACCUUGUCUGCUAAAUAAACAUGUGCCCUCAGG